AUUAGGAAGGCCCCCAGCUGUGGCCAGCCCAGGGCCGGGCUGCCCACCGUGCCAGCCCAGUUUCAAUGACCCACCUGAGGGUUUCCAUCGUGGGCCAGGGGACCGGCGCAGGCGGGCAUCCGGAGCCAGGCAGUGGCCAGCCCAUCCCGGGCAGGGUCAUAGGUGGGGCUGCAGGCCUCGAAGCCGCCAUGUGAAGGCAGCAGCGACCCCAGGCAGGGCGGGCCAGGUUGACCUUGCACCUGCUCUCCCCUCAGCCCCGCGGCCAUGCCGACCCUGGUCGUGGGCACGCCGCCCACCUGCCUGGGGGACACACCUCAGCCCUGCCACAAGAACAGCCAGAGGCAGGGCCCCUUCUCCCAUGGGGCCCCAGGGAGAGCAGCCGACUGGAAGGCUGUUGCCAAGCCCAGGCUCUGCGCACCUGCAGCUGAGGAUGACGUGGCAGCCCUGAGGUGGCCCGGGCCCUCCCAGCAGCCAGACCCACCCUGGGCAGCUCCCCACGUGGUCGGGUCUGACGACCUCAAGGAACCAGGACCCUGGGGGAAGGCGUGCAGCCUGCCCAUGUGGUCCACAGGCCCGGAGGCUAGGGAUGGGGACAGCUCGGUGUCAUCGGGCCGCCUCUCGUGCUCUUCGGGGGGCCACGACGUGUGUGUGUCUUGGAAGGAGAGGCCACCCCAGGUGUUGGGGCCCCAGCAGAGGCCCAGAAAGAGUGACGCGCGGCUGGAGCAGCUGAGAGACAAGAUCCGGGCCCAGGCGUGGCAGCAGGGGAGCUGUGCGUCCCUGGGCACCUCAGCCCCCUCCAGCGCCUCCAGACUCCACAAAGCCUCCACGCUGAUGCUUAGGAGGAAAGGCCAAGAGGCAAAAAAUCCCCCUCCAGCCCCUGAAUGCUCAGGUUUCAGCAUCUUGAGUGCAGCUGAGCGCAGAGUUGAAGCCAAGGCAUCCCACGGCCAGGGGCGCGAGCUCUCCAGGGUCUCCCAGCACCAGGUUCCUGUUCUGAGGGAAAAACCCAAAAGGGUCAAAAGCAGUUCUUGCAAAAGAGAGAAGACCCCCAAGUUGCCCUCCCCUAGAAGAGCGGCCAAAGACAAACACAAAGACGAAGAUUCGGAGCUGGUUGGUGUUUACGCCUGGAGAAAGGGACAAGCUCUGGUGAGGUCGCUGCUUGGGCCCCCUCCCGUCCUCCGCAGGCACCAUAGCAAGGAUCCCUCGAGAGACCCGGCUCUCACCGUGGACUUAGGAGACAGCGAGAAAGUCAUAGCUGCCAAGUGCUCACCGGUUUGUGCCCAGUUGCCCGAUGCCACCUCCGCCUACAGUGACCAGCAGGUGUCUGGGAACACACCCAGCCUGGCUUCCUUCGACCAGCCAGCGACCAUACAGACGGCCAUGGCCAUCCUACAAGACCUGCGCCAGCAAAUCCAGGCUGGGCUGGAGCUGGCCCAGGCCCGCAAGGGAGGGCAAGAGCUCGGGCCAUCAAAGCGGAGGCUGCAGGACGUGGCAGGGAGGGGCUGCUGCAGGGACCCCAAUGCCCAGAGCUCCUUCUCUAAGAGUCCCUGGGCCAUGACAGAGAGGAAGCAUUCCUCUUUAGAGAGGGCUAGGAGUGUCCACACCUGGGAGCCCUGGAGCUCCUCCACUGCACGGGAGUCCUGUCCGCAGAGGGCCUGGGGGGCCCAAGGACAGGACCGCUCCUUCCAGAGGCCGGAGAGUCCCCAUGAGAGGUUGGGCCACUUCUCCCAGAGGCCCUGGAGUGCACUGGCUGGGCAGGCCUGCAGUCCGCAGAGGGCCUGGGGGGCCCAAAGACAGGGCCCCUCCUCCCAGAGGCCUGGGAGCCCCCCUGAAAAGCGGAGCCCCUUCCCCCAGCAGCCCUGGAGUGCUGUAGCCACACAGCCCUGUCCACGGAGGGCCUGGACUGCCUGUGAAACCUGGGAGGACCCUGGCCCCAGACUGCGGAACCCUCUGGAAAGGCCCAGUCCUCCAGCCCAGCGGCCCUGGAGCAGCUCCGGCGUGCAGAGGGCCGGCCCCCAGGGCAAGGGCAGAGGCAUCGGCUCCCCCGUCUCGGCUGCCAAGCAUGCCCUGCCAAGGCCCACCGGGAGCUUCCCUCAGAACCCACUUGGGAAGGAGAAGGACACGCUGCGGCCCUGCCCCAGGUCCCGGGGGCUCCUGGGACCCUCGCACAGCUCUGAGUCCUUGCGGGAGUUCAUGCGCCAGAAGGCGCAGGCCCGGCGGCGGCAGGCCCUGGAGGAGAAGGCCUCGGCCCUGCGCACACGGGAGCUGAGGAGCCGGAGGCUGCAGGAGGUCUACCGGCAGCAGAGGGAGGCCGUCCUCGGCAGGGCGGUCCCCGUGGUCUCCCGGACCACCCCUGGCAUCGUGACCUUUGUCCCCAGUUCUGCACAGUCCGGGGGCCUGGAAGCCUCCGGGAGCCUGGAGUCCCCAGUGCUGGAAUGGAGCAAAGUGACCUCUGGCAUGGUGCUGGGGGGCCAGGAAGCCCCAGGCAGCUUCUGCCUGUGUUUGAACAGAGCCUGGAACCAUGCUGAGACCCUAGAUCCCCCAGGGAUGGGGGGCCCCCAAGAUGGCCGGGAUGCCCCCGUGCUGCUGUCAGCUUCACCCUCUCUGGGAUCCCUGGAGCUCCAGGACCUGACCACCCGCUACCUACCCCGGGGGAUGUGCAUCUACCUGGACCCAAAGGAGGCUGAGCACCUGGGCACUUCCAGCUCCCUGCACCUCCGGCAUAAGCAGGCGCAGCUGCAGGCGCUAGAGACCACAGCCAAAGUCCUCAAGCAGCGGGUCGAUAGCCUCACCGCCAAGCUGCAGGGUGCCGAAGCGCUGGACACCGUCAGGGACCCAGCUGUGGGCCUGCUGCGCUCGUGCCCCCACAGCCUACCUGCCGCCCCCACGCUCGCCACCCCCACGCUUGCCACCCCAGCCUGCCCUGGAGCCUUGGGGCCCAACUGGGGCAGAGGGGCACCUGGGGAGUGGGUGAGCAUGCAGCCCCAGCCCCUUCUGCCCCCGACCUACUUCCUGGACGGCGAGACACUGUCGUGGGGCCCCAGCUGGGAGCAACAGCAGAGUGUGAGCCCGAGGGCCCACUGCGAGAGCAAGCCCCGAGGUUUUCCAGAGGAGGGACACGUGGACGUGAAACCAGACAAAAGGCUGCAGAGAGGCGUGGCCCCCUUCCAGGCCCUCAGCCCCUCUGCGGGGAGCUCAUAUGCGGGCCCAGCCACGCUGCACCCUAUCUGGGGCUCCCUGGGACUGGAGGAGACGCCGUCGGUCGGAGGGGCAGAUUCUGUGGCGCCCUGCACCCCCCGGAGCUGCGGUCAGCAGGAGGACCCAUGUGUGAGAUGCCUUCCCAACACCCAACAGAAGACCUCCAGCUUUCUGGAUUCUCUGAAGCUGGACCAGCAGAAGCAGGCGUUGGCCCUCCUGCGGCAGCGGGCAGAGCUGGAGGCCCGGGAGACACAGCAGACCCUGGAUGGGCUGCUCUUCAGGAGGCGGCUGGAGGUAGCAGCCGCUUGCCACAGGGGGAGCCCCUGUCUCUGCAGGAGGUUGGGUGGGAAGCAGCUGAUGGAGAGACACUCGACCCAGGCCAGGCCAGAGGAGGCGUUGAAGCUGGAGCAGCCUCCGAUGUGCAAGGACCGAGAGCCGACCACAGCCUCUCAGAGCACAGGGAUGGCCACACCCAGGUCACACCCGCCUCUGGACACAGAUGCUGCCACGUCCUCCCAGGGUCCCGAGGACAGGCCAGAGAAUGUGGUGGCCAAGCCAGCCUCUGCAGAGGUGGAGGGCCCUGACGGAGCCCUCUCCCAGCUUCCCCUGGCCAAGUUCUUCCCUCCGGACAACCCCACCCACCAGCUGCAGAUGCUGGAGCGGAGCCUGCGGGAGGAGGAGCUGCGAGCACAGCACCAGGCCGCGCUGCUGCGCCUGCGAGAGAUGGCGCUCCAGGAGAAAACGCUCGCGGAGCUGGCCUGGCUGGAGCAUCGACGAGGGUGCCUGGACAGCAAGAGGGACAGAGCUGUGCUGGCCGCGCUGGUUGAGAAGCAGCAGCAAGCCCUCAGCAGAUUGGAGAAGGAGCAGAGGGAAAUCCAAUACCUGAGACACACGCAGCUGUUCAGGCACCGGGACAGGAAGCUGCUUCUGCAGCAUCAGAGGGACGUCGUCUCCAUGCCGGGGCCUGUGGACAUCCUCCCCAUCCCGGGGCCCACGGACGUCGUCCCAGCGCACGAGCUGCAGGCCCAGGCCAAGCUGCAGCAGGGUUCCAGCCCCAAAGUCAAGGCCGCCUGGGAGGGAGGCUCAGAGACAAGCCAGCAGCCAGAGGCCUCCCUGUGUCCCCUGACCCCAUGCAGGCCCAGCAGCUCCACCAGCCAUCGCCCCCAGAGCAGCCCCGCAAGCUCAAAGGCCACGCGCCCUCCCACUGAGCAGCAGGAUGUGACGCCACCCCAGACAACCUCCGAUGCAGAUGGUCACCAGCAGCCUCCGAGGCCAGCAUGGGGCGAGGACACACACGACCCCCAGGGCCCGCUGGUGGAGAGUGGCAGCCAUGUCAGUCAAGAGCCUGGGGAGCAGCCUCGGGCCCCUCUGCUGGGCCUGCAGCACGUGAGCCCCCCGGACGGACAGCGGCUGGGCCCAGCCUUUCCCGCCGAGGAGGCGGAGGGGCGCCUCCCCACAGCUCAGUGCAGGUCUCGGGAGGUGAAGGAGCCACCCCCAGGAGACCCUCAGACCAAGCCCGGCCCUUCCUUAGCAGGGAAGCCCCGGGCUCCAACAGACAGCCAUGUGGGGAGCUUCAGGGAACGCAGCCGACGCUCCUGCGGCAGAGAAGGUCCUUGUGGCCCACAAGAAGCCAGCCAGGUGGCUGAGGACAGCAUGAGCGAAGAGGGCUUGGAAUCGGGGCUGGAUUUUGCUGAGAGCCCCGUGGAGGAGUCCCAGGAAACCGAGAGCUGGCGAUCGGGGGAGCAGAGGUGUGGGGCUGAGCUCCCUGGAGCAGGGGUGGAGCGUGAGGCACGGAGACGGGUUCAGCCGGUACCCCCUGUCCCCCUGCUGUGGGGACCCUCACUCUCUCCUGGCACACCUGUGCUGCCGGGGCACAGCCCUGCACCCACCCUGAGCCCUCCUGGGUCUGACCCACUUUUGGAAAUAAAAAUGUCACCCAUGAAUCAGCCCAAGGUCAGCAGAGCGGCUUCGAACCCCCUGGGAGUGGCAGCCCCACCCCCCUCUCUGCCACCUGAUCCAGUGGGAUUGAGACUGGAUGCCCCCAAAGACAAGCCCUCGGGGAGCCCUUGCCCUCAGGGUCACUCAGGUGGUGGCAGAGGACUGGCUGGGAUGUUUUUCGAGUGUGAGCUGUGGACUGAGCCUGGUGGGGUCCCUGACAGUGGGCCCUGGGGAAGAGGCCAGGAGGACCAGGAUCCCCACAGGGUUCUCCACGAAUGUGCUUGCAGGACGGAGGCCUGUCAGCAGGAGGUCCCCGGCAUCUCCUCCACCUGGCUGGAGGCUGCCCAGGCCGCUGCCUCCCCAGCAGCUCCUGUGGUCCCUGAGGAGGCGGCGCCCCCAAUCCUGCACCAGGGCAGUCCCCUUCUCCCCACCACCUCCUCCUGCGGUCCAGGCUCUGAGUCUGCUUCUGGAACCUGCUGGGGGCCUUCGGAAGAAGCCACGGUGUCAUCCCACACCUCCCCAGCAGGCUCUGUGAGCAGCCUGUCCUGUCCCUCUCUCUGGGAGUUCCAGAAAGCAGCGGCUACCCUGAUCCAGCUUUCUGGGAGCUCCAGCUCUCUUCCCAGCUUGGAAGCUGAAGACUCCCCAGACGAAGGUUUCAGCUGGCCUGGAGAGCUCUCUGCCCGACACUCCUCGGGGGAAGCUGGCCUGCCUUUGUCCUGGCGGUCAAACCAGGGUGAGCCUCGGCCAGGCAGUGCUCCUGGGGGUGGAGGAUGGGUGACCUGGCAGAGGCCCCAGGGCCGCAGGGCCGGCCCCCUGCGUGGCUCCUCCUUGGACACGGCCAUGGCAGAAGUUUCAGCGCCGGAGCAAAGCCCAAAGGCAGGCUGGCUACUGCCUUUCCCAGACAUCCCCUCUCCAAGGUCAGGGUCAGAGCUGUCAGAGGCCUCCAGCAAAGUUUGGGAGGAGGACUGCGAGGAGGACCUGCCAGAACCCUGUACCGGGGCCAAGCCAGCCUCGGGGAGCUCCCUGCCUGCAGGUGGCUCACUGGGCCUUGGAAGCGGCGUGGAGCCCCAGGUGGCUCCUCCCUCCCCACGGUCCGGGGAGGGGCGGGAAGCUUCUGGGACCAGCGAGAGCCUGAAAGGGGGUGUCAGAAGCGGCAUGGAGCCCCAGGUGGCUCUUCCGUCCCCAUGGCCUGGGGAGGGGCUGGAAGCUUCUGGGACCAGCGAGAGCCUGAUGGGGGUGUCAGACACAGGAGAAGCCCUCCAGGCACCCCCUGAGGCCGCCGGUGUGGUGUUCCCGCUGCAAAUCUCUUCUGCCGGUGACUCGGACUCACUGCUGGUCUUUCCUUCGUGGACCUCUUUGAGUGAAGGGGCAGAUUUCGGCAAAGGAGGAGAGACUUCUGGCUACCAGGAGGGAACCCGGGAUGCUGACCCGAGCCCAUCCACCAAGAGCAAACUCCCGUACCUCAUGCCAGAGCCCGAGACCCCGGUGACCCUGCAGGCUCCUCCUGGGGACCCAGGCAGGCUGGCACCUCCAGUAGCUGAGAGCCGGGCGCCUGGGCCUGGUGGGAAUGGGGCCCCCACUGUCCUGGAGGAAGCCUGUCCCCUACUUGCCGGUGACGUCUUGACUGAGAUCCUGUCUCCCGUGGACGAGUUGCUGUCCUACGGCAGUGCCGACCUCCCGUCCUCCAUCCACAGGGAGGCCCCCCUACCCCCACCUCCUCCCACUCCCCAAGCACAGAGUGAUGGUGAAGACACCAACCCAUGCUCGGAUGCCUUCCCUUCCCCGCCCUCGGGGCCCCUUGAGGAGGACACCGCCAUCACCACCCAGGAUUUGUCCUCCUUGUCUGAGGAGAGUCUGCCGGAGGGACUGUUUCCUGGGCCCCAGGGGUCGGCGGGAACCCAGUAGUUGGGGCUCUGCCCAGGGGUGGCUGGUCCGGGUGGAAGCGUUGACGACCAGUUGGGUAGAUGCAGUUCUGCAGCAGGGGAUGAGGCCGGAGGCAGCCAGUGGCCUGAACCUGUCAGCUGGCCAGGGCACUCGUCGUGUGAGGGGUCAGGCAGUGCCCCUGGAGGGCUCCCAGGGCCAUCAGUGCAGCCCCCAGCUCCAUCCAGAGUGGCCUCUGUGGCCAGGGAAGGUCUGUCAGGGCUGUUGGCAGCUGGUGACGUGGAAGUGAUGAUCGGCGGACUGGGCUCCUGUUUUGGGCACAGGGUUCUGGGCUGAUGUGGCCUUUGAGGAGGUCUUGGGCAGUCGGGGAGAGCCCUGGGAAGGAGCGCAGAGCUCUGGGCAUGCAGAGAGCCGGGGUGGGUAGCGGGGCAGCUCUUAGUGGGUCUGGAUGAGCUCCUGGACACUGCCUCACCUGCGGCAGGGUCCCUGGGCAGCCGAGCCUGCUUGGCCAAGACCCCCACCAGGGGCCAAGACCCCAAAGAAAUGCUGGGUAAGAACAGGAAGGCAGCCACACCCCCACAGGCAGCCACACCUCCAUGUCCCUGGUUGGCAGCCCCGGCAGCCUCUCUCCCAGGCCAAGUGCCCUUGGCCGCCAGUGGAAAGUCUGGGUCCCUUGAGCAUGCUGGUGAGGACGUUGAGGGAGGCCUGAGCUGCCAGGUAGAGGACCCACCCAGGCCCGAGGGCUCACUGGGCAGAAAGCCGCUCCUGGAGACAGACUCAGGCCGCUGUACCCAUCUCCCAGGUGUGGAGAGAGACCAGGCAGUGGACUUGGUCUCCACGUGGCUCACCAGGAGGGUCCUGCGUGACUCCUUAGCAGCUCUCUCCACACAGGCCCCCAGGUGCAGCCCCUAGGGAGUGUUUUCUGGAACUACAGAGGUGCACAGGCGUCCACAAUGUCAUUGUGAGCUGUGUGUGGCAUACACAUGCACACGUGGGAGUAAGAACCUAGAGGCCUGGACUUUCCCAGGGUGGACCGGCCGGGCGGCCGGCUGUGCGGGACAGUCUCCUGGACCUUUCCCCGGUGGACCGGGUGGGCGGCCGGCUGUGCAGGAUGGUCGCCUGGACCUUCCCAGGGUGGACCGGGUGGGCGGCCGGCUGUGCGGGACGGUUGCCUGGACCUUCCCCCGGUGGACAGGGUGGGCGGCCGGCUGUGCGGGACGGUUGCCUGGACCUUCCCCUGGUGGACGGGGUGGGCGGCCGGCUGUGCGGGAUGGUCGCCUGGACCUUCCCAGGGUGGACUGGGUGGGCGGCCGGCUCUUCCCAGGGUGGACCAGGUGGGCGGCCGGCUCCGCAGGACGGUCGCCUGGACCUUCCCGGGGUGGACUGGGUGGGCGGCCGGCUCUUCCCAGGGUGGGCCGGGUGGGCGGCCGGCUCUUCCCGGGGUGGACCGGGUGGGCGGCCGGCUCUUCCCCUGGUGGACAGGGUGGGCGCCGGCUCUGCGGGACGGUCGCCUGGACCUUCCCCUGGUGGACGGGGUGGGCGGCCGGCUGUGCGGGAUGGUUGCCUGGACCUUCCCAGGGUGGACUGGGUGGGCGGCCGGCUCUUCCCAGGGUGGACCAGGUGGGCGGCCGGCUCCGCGGGACGGUCGCCUGGACCUUCCCGGGGUGGACUGGGUGGGCGGCCGGCUCUUCCCAGGGUGGACCAGGUGGGCGGCCGGCUCCGCGGGACGGUCGCCUGGACCUUCCCGGGGUGGACCGGGUGGGUGGCCGGCUCUUCCCCCGGUGGACAGGGUGGGCGCCGGCUCCGCGGGACGGUCACCUGAAGCCAGGCCCGGACUGCACACCUGCUUCUUCGCAUCAAAGCCACGAAGAGGCGUCCAAGAAAAGGCGUUGCAGCCCAGAGGCAAGAACAGUCAGAGUCGCCAAGAGCAGGAACGAGGACGGGGCGGAGCAGCGCCUAUGCCAGGAAGGGGGUCAUGGGGAUCAGCGAAGGCCAAGAGAGGAAGAGAGAACAUCUGGGGAAAAGAAGAGCUGGGGUGGGCCUGACUGGUGCUGACUCACACCCCUGAGCCCUGCUUAGAAGUCAGGGGCAUCUGCCUGCUUUGACUUUGGAGGCUCCUCCCACACCCAAACUGCCGGCACAUGACGUGCAGCUGGGUGGACUGGGCAUGGAUGUCUCACACCUGAGCUGCACAGACCAGAGGAAGCCACGGCUCAAGGGCCCAAGGUCAUUUCUGCGCAGCCCGCACGGCCGGGGGCUUUUCCUCUGGGGAUCAGUGGCCCAAGGUCUCUUCUGGAGCAUGCUCAGGACUUGCUGUGCCUGGAAGGCCAGGGCAGCUGAUUUCUCCUGGUGCCAUGGACUUUUCUUUGCUUCCAGAGGAUUCACUGGGACCCCUGUAAUUUCUCUGGGACCCUUUUGAAUCUGAGGGUCUCUUCUUGAAUGCGGAGUUGAUGAGCAGCGUGUUGGCCUUAGGGACAUCUGUGUCCCAGCACUGAUCCUUCCAGGAUGUGGCUUCUCCUGUCCAGGGCCUCAGGCCUCCUCCACUUCAGAGAGGAGCAUACUCCAGACUUUAUGCAUGCAGUCUGGUGGGAGGCAUCACAAAGCUGGCGUGGCAAAGCCCUAAGAUGCCAGGUCACAGGACACACGGAGCUGCCAAGGCCCUCUACCCCAUAGCUCUGGUGAGAGACCCCAGGCCCCUUAGAACCUCUUUGGGCCCCCUGCCGUGAGGCAAGAGCCCCUCUCCAGACACCCCUCGCCCGGGAGCAGCUGGACCCAGCCUGCCUUCUCCAGCCCCGGGGCGGCUGCUUAGCCCCAGGUGCCGUUAACAAUGGCCGGCCUGUGUCAGGGUCCCCAUUCACCAUGUGCACAGGAAGCCCAGCUCGGGCCAUGCAUCUGAUUUUGCACCAGCUCCUGCCCAGCCCACCUGAGAAUGCAGAUGUUUGGAUCCAGUGGGGAAUGUGUUCCUGCUCCAUGCUCCCAAUUUCAGAACAAACUUUGAGCUGAGCUACAGCUUUCUCAUUGAUCCCCUUCUAGUCUUCUGAACAAAUUAGUCUGUGAUUUUUUAUUUUUUUCCAUUUAUUGCUGACCCUUUUGGAUUUAUGAGGCCGUGUGAGAGGAAUUAUGUAUCUCACACACACGCAUCUGGCAUGACGAUAAAUCUCCACCACUGAAGCCCCGCAGAUUUGCAGCGAAUCUGAUGGCUCCCAGGCUCGCUGCCACGUGGUUGGUGCUGACGUGCGGCGCAAUGCGGUGGCGGCUGCAGUCACAGCUGGAACCAGCGUGACUUUCCCUGGGAGCCCAGCAGGUGCCUCGCGUCGCUGGCAGGUGGUAGGGUGCCCUUGAAGGGGGCUGGUCGUGAGGAACGAAGGAAAACCCGGGCCAGGGCUUCCAAGGACAGCGGCCCUGGAGGGGGCCGGAGCCGUCAGGUUACUCUGAGCACCGGAGAAAAAGCCGCUUCAGCAGAGGUGUAAACGCAUUUAAUCUCCCAACAGGACAUAUACAGAGCGGAGGGCUUUGGCAUUCAGAUAUAUUGACCGGGCAAGAUGGUAAUCCAAGGUUCCUCCCCUUCAAGGUCUCCUGCUGUAUUUGCCUGGGCUCUGAUCUGUCGUCACCGCUUGGGCCAAUAAAUCUUGAUACCAGCCUCCA